AGCAGUUGGGGCAGGAGGAAGCCGACUGCUGCCUGGUCUGCAAAGAAGUCCUUUCAAGUCUCUAGGACUGGACUCUUCCUAAGCAAGUCCGGUAUGUAGAGAAGGAAGCACCCUCACUAUGUGGCUCUACCUGGCGGCCUUCGUGGGCCUGUACUACCUUCUGCACUGGUACCGGGAGAGGCAGGUGGUGAGCCACCUCCAAGACAAGUAUGUCUUUAUCACGGGCUGUGACUCGGGCUUUGGGAACCUGCUGGCCAGACAGCUGGAUGCACGAGGCUUGAGAGUGCUGGCUGCGUGUCUGACGGAGAAGGGGGCCGAGCAGCUGAGGGGCCAGACGUCUGACAGGCUGGAGACGGUGACCCUGGAUGUUACCAAGAUGGAGAGCAUCGCUGCAGCUACUCAGUGGGUGAAGGAGCAUGUGGGGGACAGAGGACUCUGGGGACUGGUGAACAAUGCAGGCAUUCUUACACCAAUUACCUUAUGUGAGUGGCUGAACACUGAGGACUCUAUGAAUAUGCUCAAAGUGAACCUCAUUGGUGUGAUCCAGGUGACCUUGAGCAUGCUUCCUUUGGUGAGGAGAGCACGGGGAAGAAUUGUCAAUGUCUCCAGCAUUCUGGGAAGAGUUGCUUUCUUUGUAGGAGGCUACUGUGUCUCCAAGUAUGGAGUGGAAGCCUUUUCAGAUAUUCUGAGGCGUGAGAUUCAACAUUUUGGGGUGAAAAUCAGCAUAGUUGAACCUGGCUACUUCAGAACGGGAAUGACAAACAUGACACAGUCCUUAGAGCGAAUGAAGCAAAGUUGGAAAGAAGCCCCCAAGCAUAUUAAGGAGACCUAUGGACAGCAGUAUUUUGAUGCCCGUGAUAGGAGCUUUGUGGGAGUGGGAUUUGUCAAUUUCCUAUAAGAAUAUUAUUCUGAAGACCUGGAGGAGGAGGUAGCAGCAGCGGUGAAAAAUGGGAAUGACUUCUAAUAGUUUACAAUAUCAUGAAGGAAGGGCUGUUGAAUUGUAGCACAAACCUGAACCUGGUCACUGACUGCAUGGAACAUGCUCUGACAUCGGUGCAUCCGCGAACUCGAUAUUCAGCUGGCUGGGAUGCUAAAUUUUUCUUCAUCCCUCUAUCUUAUUUACCUACAUCACUGGCAGACUACAUUUUGACUAGAUCUUGGCCCAAACCAGCCCAGGCAGUCUAAAGAAAACUGGGUUGGUGCUUCUUGGAAUGAAGGCAAAAAUCUGAAAUUGUUAGUGUCUCAGUAAUCCUGAUUUAGAACCCAGGCUUUUUGUAACAAUGUGUUUUCUUGCCUAAAUUCAUUUAUCUGGCAUCAUCAGAGUACUAACAUGUUUAUAUUUCAGAUAUCCAAAGCUUACCACUUUAGGUGAUGAAUCUUUACUAUUUUAGCCCUUUUUUGAUGAGACUAUUUGUCUAAAGUGAAUCAUUUGUUCUUGCCUUAUUAAACAGAGUAGAUGGAAAACAAUUUAACCUAUUUUGAAGUCAUUUCUUUAUGAAUAUGAAUAAUUGUUCUAUGCUUUAAUAAUCUAUUGUGAGGAAACUACUAAGAAAUAUGUUGGUGUGUUUGUCCUUACUUGAAAUGGGUCUGUAUUAUGGUACUUUUAAUAAAUAUUUGAUUUUUCUUUCUCUUC